GCGCUGUCCCCCGGAGGCGUCUGGGUGUGCGGAGCGCGCGCGCGCGCGGCUCGGAGGCGCACCUGUGAGGUGUCCCUGAGGAGAGGGAGGUGGGUGCGCGGCGCCCGCGGCCUGGGGCGCUGACUCCCCUCACUUGGAGGCGCCCUGCGUCCGGCAGAGGAGGCGAGCAUCCCGCUCAGGUGAUGAGGAACCCCUCGCGCACCCAGCGCAGAAGGCUGCUGCCGCCGGACGCCUCCAUUGUUUGACCACAACAAGGGCCGGAUUCUCACCCAGGCCGCACUUGGUGAGAGUCUUCACGGACCACAGUGUUGCACGAGGUGAUUGUGUUUGCAGAGGUUUUUUUGUCCUUGAAGAGCACUUAGGGCUGGAGAGCAAGACACAUGCUGACGAGCAGAAGCUGACAGGCUUGCUGCCAUGUGGGAAAGUCCUUGGACGAGUUGUCUGCUUGCGGAGAGGUGUCUGCGGCUCAGCCCCCCUCCCAACUCCCAAAUCCCCCGGCGUCGGAGAUGAGGCCCCGGAUGCUGCCAGUGUUCUUUGGGGAGAGCAUCAAGGUGAACCCGGAACCCACGCAUGAGAUCCGCUGCAACUCUGAGGUCAAGUACGCCUCGGAGAAGCAUUUCCAGGACAAGGUCUUCUAUGCGCCCGUACCCACCGUCACGGCCUACAGCGAGACCAUCGUGGCAGCACCCAACUGCACGUGGCGCAACUACCGCAGCCAGCUGACCCUGGAGCCACGCCCGCGCGCCCUGCGCUUCCGCAGCACCACCAUCAUCUUCCCCAAGCAUGCCAGGAGCACUUUCCGGACCACCCUGCACUGCAGCCUGGGCCGGCCCAGCCGCUGGUUCACCGCCAGCGUGCAGCUGCAGCUUUGCCAGGACCCUGCCCCCAGCCUCCUGGGCCCUGCCACGCUCUGACGGGGCUGGGGCCGGCCCGGGGUGCUGGAGGAGCCGGGAGCCCUGGGGAGAAGCCGGGAGGAUGGACACGAUGAGCUCGGCCUGGCACUCGGGCAGGAGGCGGGAAGGGAGGCUGCCAGACCAAGGACCCGUGUGGAAGGAGGCGGCUCCCCGCUGCCUGCCCUGACCUACAGGCUAGGUGGUGGUCUCCUUGUUUUGGUGUCAAGGACUCAGUAAAAGCAUCUAUUUUUUUAGCACUUAAGCUGGCAAGGCGGUAGGGGCAUGCACUGUUAGGUGGUGGCCACCCCCAGGGUCAGGGGAAAAGAAUGGGUCCAUGGAGUGCCCUUGAAGCAGAGAACAGCCCCGAGCAGUGUGAGGACAGAGGCAUCCCAGCCUCAGCCGGUGGGGACGGCUGCCACUCCCCCAGAGCCCUGCCACCCCAUGUGUCCUAGGCUGGUGGCCAAGGCCAUGUGUGAGGGAAGAGGGGUACCUCUCUUCCCUGCUGCUGGCCUGGGGUAUUUCCAAAACAGCCUUUUCGCACACAUGCAGGUUGCACCGAGAGGUCUGGAGCUGUGGCUGAGCCACCUCUGGCGGAUGUUGAGCCAGGAGGUUGGGCAAAGGCCGGAUGCUGAUGCCAGCGCUGGAGGUGGUGAUACUGGGGGCGGGGAAGGCCUAGAAAUACUUUGAGCCAUGGCCUUGCCAGUGUCCCGUGCCCUCCAGUGUCAAAGAUUUGGGGCACUGCCCGUCGAAAUGGAAAGGUUGGUGCUCAGCCUCUGGAGCCUCACCUGCAGGGCGUCCCCAGCUAACACCCAUCCACGCACCACCUCCAGGACGAGAACCCUUGAUGUCAAAACCAAGUGCCCAGUGGAGGCGGUGAAGCUCUCGGAAAUGCUGCCACCUGUGUGAGGCCGGGUCUGAACUCGAGGGAGUCGGAGCUCAGCUGUCGGUUUAAAGAGACACUGAGGGGACCGGGCUGCCGCCCUCAGCCUGCAUUCCUGUGCGCAAUCGAUUCCGCAAUGACAGCACCUUACUCCUUCCUGCGGCAGGCUCACCCCUGCCUGUGGGAUGUUGUGAGAGGAACAUGAGCCAGACAAAGACUUGGCUCAGGGCUCCGUGGAACAAGCCAGGAUGCACGGGGAGCUGGGGGAGCCCCCAGCCUGGGGCAGCCCAGCAGGCCGCUGAACAAACACCCCAGAAGCCAGCACUGUGGCAGGGUGCUGGGGAGAUGCCCCUCUGAGCCUUCCUCCCCCCUCAGACCUGAAUGCACUCCACAGUUGGGGGCUGCCCCUGCCACUCCCCUGGUAAUGCAUAAAAGGGGAGGGGAAGGUUCCCUGGGGCUUGAGCUCCCUCUGUGGAGGUGAGGAGGGGAGAUUCCGUUCACAUCCAGGAGGGGCAAAAUGACUGAUGUAUUUUUAUGUAUCUACACAGAGAGUGCAUUUUCUCUCCAGAGAUGCUGUCUGGUUAACAAAGGAAUAACUUAAGAAAUUGAUUGAUUAUCUUAAUAAACUGUGCAAACCCAA